AUUUAAGUGCGUUCAUUCUCACUGCUGUUAUUGUUUUCUGACAGCAUGCCUGAACCAGCUAAGUCAGCUCCUGCUCCGAAGAAGGGUUCCAAGAAGGCUGUGACCAAGGCGCAGAAGAAGGAUGGCAAGAAGCGCAAGCGCAGUCGUAAGGAGAGCUACUCCGUGUAUGUGUACAAGGUGCUAAAACAGGUUCACCCCGAUACUGGCAUCUCAUCCAAGGCCAUGGGCAUCAUGAAUUCCUUCGUUAACGACAUCUUCGAACGCAUCGCAGGCGAGGCUUCCCGUCUGGCCCACUACAACAAGCGCUCGACCAUUACCUCCAGGGAGAUCCAGACCGCCGUGCGUCUGCUGCUUCCCGGAGAGCUGGCCAAGCACGCAGUGUCCGAAGGUACCAAGGCUGUCACCAAGUAUACAAGCUCCAAGUAAAUGUGUGCUUAGGUGCUUUAAAACUCAAAGGCUCUUUUCAGAGCCACUCAAGUCUCACAUAAA